CCUUCGCCACGCCGCCGCGCAGCCCCUCCAUCUUCCUGCUCGGCACCGGGCCCCGCGCGCCCCUGCCUACGGGGUCCCGCUGCUCUCCGGGGCUCCUGCCAGCCCCAACCCCCGGCCCCGGUGGCCUCCCCCCACCCCCGCCCGGGUCCCCCUCCUCCGCCACACGCGCGCGCGCUCACACACACACACACACACACACACACACACACACACAUAUAUACACGCCAGCGAGCUGCUGGCCGCUCAAUGGACCGAUUUCCCCGGUUUCCCUGAACCCAGCCCAGCCCGGGAUGAGAAACUGCAAAAUGGCCCGGGUCGCCAGUGUGCUGGGGCUGGUCAUGCUCAGCGUCGCCCUGCUGAUUUUAUCGCUCAUCAGCUACGUGUCCCUGAAAAAGGAGAACAUCUUCACCACUCCCAAGUACGCCAGCCCGGGGGCGCCCCGAAUGUACAUGUUCCACGCGGGAUUCCGGUCACAAUUUGCGCUGAAGUUUCUAGACCCGUCAUUCGUGCCCAUUACGAAUUCUCUCACCCAGGAACUCCAAGAGAAACCUUCUAAGUGGAAAUUUAAUCGGACAGCGUUUUUACAUCAAAGGCAAGAAAUUCUUCAGCAUGUCGAUGUAAUAAAAAAUUUUUCUUUGACCAAGAAUAGUGUUCGGAUUGGACAACUGAUGCACUAUGAUUAUUCCAGCCAUAAAUAUGUUUUCUCUAUUAGCAAUAACUUCCGGUCACUUCUUCCAGAUGUGUCACCCAUUAUGAACAAGCAUUAUAAUAUUUGUGCUGUGGUUGGAAAUAGUGGGAUCCUGACAGGGAGCCAGUGUGGACAAGAAAUAGAUAAAUCAGAUUUUGUUUUCCGUUGCAAUUUCGCCCCUACGGAGGCUUUCCAAAGAGAUGUUGGAAGAAAAACCAAUCUUACCACCUUCAACCCCAGCAUCCUGGAAAAAUAUUACAACAAUCUCUUGACUAUUCAGGACCGUAACAACUUUUUCCUCAGUUUAAAAAAGCUUGACGGGGCCAUUCUUUGGAUCCCUGCAUUUUUCUUCCACACUUCAGCAACUGUGACCAGGACAUUAGUUGACUUUUUUGUUGAACACAGAGGUCAGUUAAAAGUCCAACUGGCUUGGCCGGGAAAUAUAAUGCAACAUGUCAACAGGUACUGGAAAAACAAACAUUUGUCACCUAAACGGCUGAGCACAGGUAUUCUUAUGUACACCCUUGCAUCAGCAAUAUGUGAAGAGAUCCACUUGUAUGGAUUUUGGCCGUUUGGAUUUGACCCCAACACAAGGGAAGAUCUUCCAUACCAUUACUAUGACAAAAAAGGAACCAAAUUUACCACCAAGUGGCAGGAGUCCCACCAGCUGCCUGCUGAGUUUCAGCUGCUGUACCGAAUGCAUGGGGAAGGGCUCACCAAGCUGACUCUGUCACACUGUGCCUAAGAACUCCAAACGGAAAGCGCCAAAUGGCUGUUUAAAAAGUGCCCCAAAUCAAAUUGAAUAGCCUUCAGAAUAGAACCCUAGAGAAUGUCUUAUAAGGAUUGUCUGCCAUUUAAAAGGAAAGAUGUCUUUUCUCUUUUGCACUGCUCUUUUAAGAGUUUUAGCAGAUUUAGCAGGACAGAUGCAUUGAAGCCACAUGGUUUAGACUUGAUUGAUAAAGGGAAUGUUGCAUUUGGGACUAUGCUGCUAACGAAAUGGUUUGAAGUAUUUUCAUGUUUGGAUUUUAAUAAUAAACUGCCUCUCAUUUUUAUGAGGACUAGAGCUAUAGUUUCUGCAGCUCUGCUCAGAUAGUCCUCAUAAUCAGAGGCCUCUGGCCAACUGGGGCAGGACCUGUUUUGCUGGUGGGAUCAGACUCUGAAAAAUGGAAACGUAAAAAACUGGUUUGCAUAUCUCAUCUUCUAUCUAUCUCCCUAUCUCCAUCUCUAUCACCAUCUCACUCCUUCCCUCUGCAACUACUCCCUGCCCUACCACCGUGGAGUUUAAUAAUUUGCUAGGAAUCCUAUUGAAUUCGCUUUGCUUGUAUAUGUUGCAUUUGUACUUGAUGUGUUUAAGGUUCUGGGUAACUUUGAUGCUUCAUGACAAAAUAGGCAAAUCACGAUGGACUCCCUUGUGAUUCCUUUUUUAAAGAAAUGCCUCUGAUGCAGUCCUCACCAGUCCAUUCAGUCAUUCUACAGCAAGAUGGUCCCUCUGUGGUGAGUGGGAUAUAAGGCAGUGCAUCUUUCAUGAUCACAAAGAAAGCCUAUGUUGUGGAUAGCAUUGCGUCUCUUGAUGUAGGCAUUGUUAUGGCAAAUAAUAGCACUGUGGCCACAUCUGUAAGGCCAUUCCAGCCUAAAUUUAGUGUCUCCCAUAAUCCCAACCCAUGCACUAGGCUGGGUGUUCUCUCAGAAUAUAGAGGCAAUGAAUCAGCUUAAGACCCUGGGACACACAAAGGAAAAGGAAGAAGAAUAUUUAGAAGUUGUUAUGGAAUCCUGUGUACCCUAAAGUGUGGUAACCAUGUUACCCAUUCCAGCUGGGUUAAAGUGGAGGAGGAUCUUGGCCAGGCCAGGUGCCCAGGUGACUAGUGCUGAGGUGCGAUCGUUUUCCGUAUCAUUGUGUGCACCACCACCAAUCCAGAACCAUUUGCUCUCUUUGAGAACAUUGUAGCACUGGAUAUUCCCUCUUUCCACUGAAGUCAGAUCUAUACAACUACAAAUUAAGCAUUUCAAAAGAAAAAGCCAUUGUGCAGUGGCAAGAGUUGGAAUCCAAGAUUAUGUAGACCUGCGAUGAAGGAAGUAGCUGGCCAUUCUCAUUUUCUUUAUUUCAGCCAUAUGAGUAGAAAUCAAAUCAUUCCCAUCCCUGGCUUUUUACUGAGCAGCACUUUGUUCUUCCAAUUCAGCCCAACGUCUGGCCAAGUUGAUGUUAAAUUUUAAUAAGAGUUUCUUUCUUCUUUCCAAAUGCCAGUCAAGCAUAUUUGUUAUGCAUUUGAGUGGGGUAGCUCAUUCUUUUCCUGAAAUCUCAUCUAGAUUGCUUGCAAUGCGACAAAUAACUGUUUAAAAAAUGUGCUGUAGUUCAGUGAUGAGCUCAUUGCCCCUCUUUAGGAAGGUAAGAUCAUGCCUAAAAUUAAACCGAAUAUGGUAAGGAAAGACACUAUCGUUAUGCUCACGUUCUGCCUGGUCCUAAACCUGCCUUAUUAUUAUUUUCAGAAAGCAAUCUAAUUAGAGCAACUUGCAUAGAUCUAGAUAUUAACUAAUGAAAGAAACACCAAGUUCAAAUGUGUUACCAAUUAUGACACACAUUACAAUAUAAUUAUAAGGGGAGACAUUAAAAACAUUUUGUAAUUCAGUGGUAUAAUUUGAUGGGUAUCACAACCACACCGUGUUUGUUCCCUGUCCCUUUGAAGAGGACUGUACUACCAUCCUCACACUGUGCUCUGUUGGGAUCACUGAGAGAUUGACAACUGACAGAAGUGUUUAGUUGGCUGUUCCUGAGCACUUAGUUCAUUUGGUUAUAGCUAAGUGAUAUUAAUGCCAAUAUUACUUGGGCCAGAUUCUGACUCUGGAGUUUUAAUCCCAAUGUGCCCAUUCAUUUUCACUAAAUAUAAAUGCAUAGACACUUUAAACCAAGAAGAUUAAAAGAGGAAAAGACCAGAAUCUCUAAAAAACAGUUUACUGUUCUGUAGUGGACAAUUUAAAUUUUAUCUCAUCAUAAUGCCAAGGAUUUUUGUUUGUUUUUUAAGUUCAGGGAGAUUUUUUAAAUCUCCUUGCAGUCUUGGCUCCAUCUUAACCUUAGAGUGGGAGGACUUUCCCAUCCCCCACCACCGUGUUAUCUAUCACUUUAAUGAAAACUCAAAAUAGUGAGGAAAUGGACUUUUCUUCAGAACUUGAGGGGUUUAGAGAUCAGGCUCAUCUCUGCUUAUAAGGAGGACUUCCUGGAGAUGAUCCCAAUAGAUCACCCUUCACUUUUGAAGAAUAGCAGCUUCUAGCUGACCAUGCAAAAUCUCUGUUUGUUUUUAAAGACUGUUUCAAAGAUUAAAUCUAUACAACCACUUUUAUGACCAAAAAAGUUGUUGUGUCCCAAGUGUCCUAAUUAGAAAGGCAGCUGGCUCUCCUGCAGCUCCCAGGCUUGUGUAGUCAAGUGCAGUGAACUGGGCAGUAAUCAGCUCAGGACCAUUGGCUCUUUCCUCCUCUUUCAGCUACAGACACAUGCCCUGGCUUUUGCAUUGACCUUGCUUUGUUAGUUCUAGACUAAUUUAUCCUUUUGUCAGACACUUUCCCUUUUUUAGGAUACUCACAACAGAGUCCACUUUCAGCUAUUGGAAUACAUUUUACCAUAAAGCCCCCAAGGCUUUCUACCCAUAACACCAACACAAAAAACCAAUUAAGUUGCAGAGGGGGGAAAUAAUCACAAACUUUUGGCAACCUGCUUAAUGCUAGACGCUCUGUUUUCACUGGUUAUUCUGAGUGUCAUAUGCAGAUGCAGAUCCAAGGGAGACAGGGCUAAAUGGUGGUGUCAAGAAUUCCUCCCACACCCCAAAAAUUCUUUCCAAUAUUUGAUUAUUAAAAUAUCUAUCAUUUCUCCACCUUGUGUCUGUGUCUUAAGUGUCUGUGAAUAUUGUAAAAGUGCUGUAUGUUUAGUAGUGUUGUGUGCCUGGCAGUGCUGACUAUGACUACUGUGCCAUCUGUCUGUGACCUUGAUGUCAGGUACCUGGCCAUGGGGCUACCAGCAAGGAUGUGCAAAGGAAGAACCGCUGCCCCUGCCCUCAGCUUCCUUAUGCCCGAGCCACUACUUAUCCGUGAAUGUGAGUGCCAAGAGAAACCUAAUUUGGUGGGGAAGCCAAGGAAUGGGAGAACGUUUUUUCUGAUUUGAGUCAAGGCACUAAUUAUUAGACACUCUCAGACAACAAAGCGGUAUUGACCUGAGAUCAAAGGAAGCAGGGACAAUAUUGUAGAAUGCUAGGACACUGGAAAUGAAGAGGCCUUCAGCUUCGCCAGUCUUGAUUCUUGACUUUACAAAUGAGAAAAUGGAGAAACAGGGAGGCUAGGUGAUUUGCCCCAGAUGACACUGUCAAUUAGUGGAGAAAUUAUGAUUCCUCCUCUAGUACUUCUUGGUCUUACCAGCAUCAAAUGAAGCUGGGCUCACAGGGAAAGUGGUUUUUGGUCUGGGAUCUGCAGAGCACAUAAAAUAAGUUAGAAAGUCUAUAAAAGAGGAAAAAAGGUUCUCCUCUCCCUCCCAAAAAUGACUUCCCAACACAGAACAAUAAAGGAGAUGCUUGUGUGGGUAUGCAACUGUCCACCAAUUAUCACCUACCUUCUCCCUGAGAUGAAACAAAACACGCUUGGUAAAUCAUGAUUUGAUAAAUAACAAUUAAGUUACUGGUGGUUCAUGCUUGACAGCUGCAAUCUUACCCAAUAAGCUAUUCAUCUUAGUAAAACCUUGUUUUAGUAAUAUACAUGCAUAAUUUAGAAGUUGAAGGCUGAAAAUUGUUGUGUUCUUCUCCAUAUAUAUACAACUUUCAUCGGGGUCCCUUGAGUUAAGAAAUGCCUUCUAUUUUAUAGGUAAUCUCAACAGCAGACUUUGAAAUAUUGUGUUUGGUUCAAUAUGCUAAGAAGAUAUACAAAUAAUAAUAACUUCGUGAGUCUUCAUGUGCAAAAUGACAAACUGAGCAAUUUUCUGUAUAAUUCUAGAUUCUUAAAACCUUUUUUCCCAUAAUUGUUUGAAUGCACUAGGCACAAGUUUCUGUUUAAGCCUCUGCUUCUCCCUGAAUGUGUAGAACUGUCACUUUGCUUACAAAGGGGCUGUGUGUUUGUGGCUGGCAGCCCAGAUAGAGCACUCUGGGUGCUGGGGAUUGAGGGCACCUUGGCCAGCUGAUUGACCUGUCUGGACUCUGUGGCCCAAUUAAUCGAGGCCACAGAUCAGUUGGUACUAAGCAUCAAAAUGAUUCAUUAUGCCUCUCUCACACUCCGAUUGCUUUGCCACAUAGAUAACAGCAUUUGAAAUGGGAAACACUUUAGAAUGUCAUUAUUGUAUUAUAUAUUGUCAUCUUAUGCAGUAUUUCUGAAAAUUUAUUUUUAUUGUGAUGACUGAUUGAAGACAUAUGUGUAUGAAUAGAUGUUCCUCAGUGAAGCCUAUUCUCUUGUUGUUGAUGACAGUGGCAUCAGAGUGAAGAGUUGUUGCAGAGUAACUGACUUCAGUUUAAGGUUACCCUGGGGUUCUGGGGUUAGGACCCGGAUUAUGCAGCUGAUCUCCCAGCAAACACAGCUGUAUGAAAUAAGCAACUCUUCAAAAUACAAUUCUUGCCACUCAUUCUGGACCUUUGAUUCAUAAUGUCCUGGGAUAAGUCCAACUUACAAAGAUUCCCAGGUGAUUCGUGUGACCACCAUUUGGAAACCAGUAAUAUAUACAUCCGGAGUCAUAUAUACCAUUUUGAACAAAGUAGCUAAAUGCUUAUCUCUCCUUGUGCGAUUAGUUUCACAUGUUCGUUGAGGUUAUCAUGUUAAAUGGCAAUAUAGACACAGUCUUAGUGAUUCAACAAUUCAGCUGUUUCAGCCGAAUUGACCAGUUGCUAAUUUAUAAGCAAAUUGUAACUGAUCAAUUUAGUCAGAAUGGAUGCAAGCCCAAAGACAAGGUGGAGAGCAAGCUUUAAUAUACACUUUGUCUCAAGGCCAGCUCUUCAUAUUUCCCUCUUUAUAUUUCAAACUAAGAGGCAGAUCUCAGGUCACUCAUCUUUAGAAUUGGUGAGAAUGAGAAACAGGGAACUGAAGUGAUUCAUUCAGAUUCAAUUUGGAAGUCAUUCCCAGAGCCUAAAAUAUUUAUCUAAGGGGUCUGAUUUAUCAACCUCAGGUAGUCUCCAAAACACAAAGGUAUUCAGGCUAAAAUAAAACCAAUCAAAAAAGGAAAUUCAGGAGGCUCCAGUUCUAAGACUAACCCAGUAUAACAAGGGUGAUCAGUUAUUACUUGUGGCCUUGUACCACCUCUGUUGGAUAAUGUGCCACCGUCCUAAUGAAGCUUUGGCCAGACUUCUUUCUAUAGCUGUGCACAUAGAAAGGCUUUAGACAACAGUGAUACCAAAGGGUUCCUUUGAUUUUCCUUCUGUGUGAUUCUCAGACAGUUUUAGCUCUUUGGUGUGCUGCCAAAUGUUUAACAACUGGCUCUGGAAAACAGUGGAACCCAGAUUUUUAGCACCUACCAAUUUCUAUGGUGUAAAUACUCUCAUCUCAGCCAAUUUCAGGCUACUAACUUAAUGUCAACCAGCUGAAAACACAACAAUAUGUUUUCAAGAGCCAGUAUAAGUUGGCUCCAAUACAGCAUGAGCCAGCUCCAGCAUAGCACUGCCUGAACAAUUUUUAAGUCAGUGAGUACCAAAUAGGAGAGGCUAGCAGAGGCUUUGGAGGGACUUUUAAAUGUCCCCUCCACCAAGGGAAGCAUUUCCAUGUUGGUUAGUUUUACUGAUUUUUAGUAAAAGAGCAUAUUAUUGGAUCCCAAGGUGUUCAAAUAUUCCACGUGACUCUUAGGAACCUCUCAACAGACUCCCCAGUAUCUUGGGAGAUUACCAACUGUGGCUUUUCUAAUUUCUAAGGGUGACCCUCCAGGAAAACAUUCUUUAAUUUAACUACCAGUUAAAACCAUGUUUGGCUGAUCUUUUUUAAAAAAUCUAUACCUAUAGUUCAUCACUUGUUUCCCCAACUUUGUCAUUUUCCCUAUCCACUUGCCCCUCAUCCUUCUGACACAAUAAAAAAAAUACAGGUACCCACAAAACAGUGCCUGCAAAGGAGCAGGGGAAGAACAAGGCACCCAGUAAGCUCACUUGGCUCUACAUAUCUGGAAAGGCACUGAGGUUCCAAGGUCUCUACCCCACCAGGGGACACCCAGUAAACAUCACGCUGAGAGUUUAAGUUGCACUCAACUGGAGUUGAUUUGCCCUUAGAAAAGUUUCCAACGGUGAAGAAAUACCACUUGGUAGGAAUAUCUCUGGGCAACUUCAUUGCUGACUGGGCAAACUUUGUAGGAUAAGGUGUCAUGUGAUGUAAGGCUGGACCAUGAAAAACAAAAAUCUACUAAUACACAUUUGGCCCCUGCAGUCCCCUGGCAUUGAGCAAUAGAGCAACUGUCCUUUCUCACCACUAGUUGUGAGUGUACUUCCAACUGAGUGUUUAGAAAUCAGGUAAUCUGGUAAUCCACAGAACAAGCUUUGUUUGCAAAUUGCAAAUUUUUCUGGUAGAAGUCAUUCUUAGGUGGGCUUCAUUAAAUCUUUGGAGAGGCAAUGCUGGGAAAAAAUAUGCCUAAUUCCUAGGACACAGUGAGUGGCCGUAAGUUGUUAUCUGCAUGUACUAAAUCAAAAUUAGAUCAUGAAGGACCAAAUCUACUUCCGUUGCUAUAAUAAAAUACCCUACAGGUUCUGUAAGGCAUUUCUAAACUGUAAAUGCUUGAAACGCAAGUUGGACAUUUUCUAUACUAUGUGUAAAAUGCCAGGUUAUACCUCUAUUUUCUUUCUUCCUAAUGGUCAUUGAAAUGAGCUUGUUUCUCUACAUUGAGCAAGCUACAUUUUAUUUUAAAUGAGUCAGGUGCAUGUUCAGAUGUCUGUAUUCCCAAUACAUUGCAUGCAGCCUGAGCACAAGUAUGCCUUCACCCUCUGGCUCUUUUCCUGACACCAAACAGAGAAGUCCACAGCUACAAGCACAAGGGGCUUGACAGGUAGGCCUUGUUUUAUUAUGAACAAAUUCACCAGAAAACCAUUCUUGAGGAACCAGCCACUCCCAUAGCAUUUUUAGUCUUAGGGAAGAAAAUUGGCAGGGAAGAAAAAUUGGCAGACAAUGGGAAAGAGGUUUGGUCAACCUGCAUAAGUGGAAUAAAGUCAUUGAAGUACUUGCAAAAAGAAGAGGGAGGUUUCCCUCUGAAGGAAUCUAGACCAUUUUUUAAUAUGGAGAAUAACUGUACCCCAUGUUAGAAGUGCUCUUUAGCCAUAUUUCAAGAUCCAGAUCUGAACCCAUACUGUGCAGAAAAGCACAAGAGCGCUUACAGCCAAGAGCCCUGGGAGGAGUUGAGUAACAGGCUGAGAUCCGGUCACCAAGCAUCAUUAGUUAGCACUGAAAUUCUCCCAGGACACAAAACAAAUGUAUGGAAACAUCGCAAUACACUAUCAUUUACUCACAUGGGACAACCACCUAAGUCCAUAGCAAAACUUUACAGAUCUAGAUGUUAUCUCAAGUCAGGAUUCCAGAUCAACAUCCUCCAUGUGGAGAUGAGACAACUGAGGUUCAGAAAGUUGGAGUGACUUAUUUGCCCAGCUAGCUAACUGGAAUUAGAGUCUGGGUCUCCCAACCACUGAUUCUGCUACACCACACUGUGCUGCUUCCAUUAGUUAGAUGGACAUUGACAAUUAAUUGUGAAAGCAUUAAUUAGAAGUCAAGACAAAAGAAUGUUUGUGAUAUCUUCUCUCGCUUAACAUACUUUGAUUUCACCAUUGCAUUUCAGCAUUUUAAAGAAUAGUGUAUCAGUAUAGAAGGAGGAGCAAAGCUCUUUAAGAGUAAUGAUGAAACCAAAAGGUCAAAAAGUAGAAGAAUAGCGAAUGUAAGUUAUUAAAUAAAUGAGCAAGAAGUAUGUGUCAGGGAAAAUAAAUGCUUCUUAUAUUGUUAAUACCGUGAUUCCCUGCCCGCUCACCCCGUCACUCAACACUUGAUGCAUUUGUUUUGGAAAGUGCCAUUUUAUGCUGAGAUACUGGUAUUGAAAACUUCCCUCUUUCCCAACUCUGUCAGAAGUUCUCUUGCUCUUUGGAAGAAGCCGAGGGCCUUAACAAAUCAGACUGACCUCCCUUGUGACAGGCAGCCUCGCCUGCCCUUGGAAACAAGCUGCCAGAAUGUGAGGGCCACAGAGACCCAAGAGAAGCCAGCACUGCUAGACUGAGGAACUUGUAAAUAUCUUCUGCUUUCUUGGUGAACAAGGACAGAGGCAAUUGCGUGUAUAUUGUGACUGUAGUUUGUGAAGAAAAUGCAACCAUUUGCUUCGACAGCUCCUCAAAUGUACUUGUUAAGUGUGAAUGUGCCUGCCUCAUUGCCUUGUGUUCCAAACACAGUACUGAAUGCGUUGUUUUUAAAUAAACCAUUUCGUUUUGCUUUGGGAAA